ACACGACUGAGUGUGCCUACACUGGUCCCACAGGUUUUCAGCUGUGGAGUUUGGGAUCUGAGCUUGGAGCCCAUUUGUUUCUGGCAGUUCCGCUCAUAUUUUCCACUUGAAGACAUCGCCUCCCUUCCUUCCAAGCUGGGAGACCAGAAGUCAACAACAGGAGGGUGGAGAGGCCGGGUCUCACAAUCCGCUUGGCUGGGGAGUCCACUGAGGUUCUUGCAUCCUGAAGCAAACCAUGGAGAGCUGGUGGGGACUUCCCUGUCUUGCGUUCCUGUGUUUUCUAAUGCACGCCCGAGGUCAAAGAGACUUUGAUUUGGCAGAUGCCCUUGAUGACCCUGAACCCACCAAGAAGCCAAACUCAGAUAUCUACCCAAAGCCAAAACCACCUUACUACCCACAGCCCGAGAAUCCCGACAGCGGUGGAAAUAUCUACCCAAGGCCAAAGCCACGCCCUCAACCCCAGCCUGGCAAUUCCGGCAACAGUGGAGGUAGUUACUUCAAUGAUGUGGACCGUGAUGACGGACGCUACCCGCCCAGGCCCAGGCCACGGCCGCCUGCAGGAGGUGGCGGCGGUGGCUACUCCAGUUAUGGCAACUCCGACAACACGCACGGAAGAGGGGGCUAUAGACUCAACUCUCGUUAUGGAAAUACUUAUGGUGGAGAUCACCAUUCAACGUAUGGCAAUCCAGAAGGCAAUAUGGUAGCAAAAAUCGUGUCUCCCAUCGUAUCCGUGGUGGUGGUGACACUGCUGGGAGCAGCAGCCAGUUAUUUCAAACUAAACAAUAGGAGAAAUUGUUUCAGGACCCAUGAACCAGAAAAUGUCUGAAGAUGUUAAGAUCCCCUGAUUACUUUGAGAAAAACAACUAAAACAAGAACCGUGUUUAUCACUGUUGUGGAGAUUUCCUUUUAUUCUUGACACAAUUUGAUGACCUAAAGUGUGUUUUCUUCUGUGUAAAGUACAUGAGCUGCCUCACUAAGCAUUCCCAACUCAUUGAAUGUGAUGUGGUUAUAAAGAUAAGUUAGGCAGCUAGACCCUGCGUUCUAAAAAAGGAUUGCUUGCAAUGUUGGUUUGGCUAUUCAUUUGCACAAAGAGACUGUGGCUCUCUGUUGUGAGAUCUUCAGCUACCUCAUGGUGCAAUAACACACACACGCUUAACCAUGUUGAUGGCACAAAGCGGUGAGCAGUAGGGAGGUAGAAUAUCUUGGUGGGGAGGGGAUGUUAUCAGCUUCUGGGAGAUGAAGAAUAUUGUUGAGGUUCCAAAGAUGCUGGACCUGUGCUAAAUUCUUCAGUGAUAUGAAAAAAUCAUUGAGCAUUCAUUAUUGCGAAUGAAGUGGGGAUGCAUUAUUUCUGACACCCACAAGCAGGGUUUGAUCAUCCUUUCAGCUUUGAGAUAUCUGCACAUAAAAUUAUUAUUACCUGAAGAAAAUAAGGCUGCAUUUUGAAAUGUUAAGUGCAAAAUGACUGAUGUUAAAACCAUCUGGGGGAAAUCUUGGGAUGCUUUUUCCUAGGAAAUCAUAUGGUUGUGAUAUGUUUUGGCGCAUAGGAGACAGAAAUAGUGAUUAUCAGGCGUUGAGCCUUUUUGUAGUAUUUUUAGUCUUUGAUACUCUGUAAGUGCUAGUUCCUAAGGCACCAACAUUGCAUUCCUUGGUUUAUACUUUUUCUAUUCAUCAGGGUAGGAAGUCUUAAAUCCUUAGGCAUCCAAGAAGUAUACUAGCUUUUUGCUUCUCUUUUAGAAAUACUUGUGGGGAGAGAAAAAAGGAUGGUUUGGGCAUAUUGGUAUAGUUUGAGUAAACUAAGGUUAAUGUUCAUAUAACAUUUAGACUUUGCCAUAAAUAUCAGAACCAAAGAUCAAGACAUUCAUGUACAGUCUGGAAUGUAUAUAUGGGGCCCAUAAAAAUUCCCAGUAUGCAUGUUUUAUGCUCACCAUUAUGAAUUGGGGUCUUCAAAGAGAGAAGGUUGAAAGUGGAAAGCACUUGAAAGGGCUCCCCGGUUUGUAAAAUAUCUUUAAUCAUUCACAUUAGGUACCUCGGAGUUGCGGGUCUCAAAUGUGGAUUCAUGCAUCAUUUGUGCAGUUUGAAGAUAGUCCAUAUUUCCUAUUUCAGUAUUAGGUCCUGCAACACUUUUCAAUUCUUGUAGAAGGUUUUUUUCAGGAGUGGUGAUGUCUGAUGCUCAAUUACUAUUUUCCCUAUAAGAGUUUCAGCAUGAGCUUAAUUAAAUUCUUGUGAAAAAACCUGUGUUUUUAGUUACACACACACACACACACACACCUACUUAAAUGGAAUCUAAACAUUUUUAGCCUUUAAUCCAUUCCAUUUUCUAAAACUGUCAUAAACUAUUUUUAAUCAUUUUAAAUAAAUGUAAAAGAAAAAUAACUGGAUUUGAUUAUUGAAUAGUUUUUUUCUAUAUUUCACAAAUAAAUUGUAUGAAAUGACUGUAGAAGUGGCCCCAAAAUUAUGAACCUUCGUAGCUGUGAAUAUGAUGCCAUAAAUCUCUUUUAAAGCUCAAGAUAGACUAUGAACAUAUGAAAUACAUAGUUACCUAAUCAUGAGACUAAAUUCACCUGGGUGACAAGGCUAACGUUCAAGCUACUUAAGAUGAAAAUAUUUGAAUCAUGAUUGCUUGGGGGAACCUCUCUUUGAGGGGUCAUGAGGACCACCUGCUGGGCAUUCUGUUUUCAUGCUGAGAAGGUGAGAAUUGAACAGAUGAGAAAAGCCUUGAUAAAACGUCAUCUCCAUGUAAUUUAGAGAAGGAUAACCUUGACUGUACAGCUGACCCUUGAACAACACAGGGCUGAACUGCACAUGUCCACCUGUAUGUGAGUUUGCUUCUGGCUCUGCCAUUACUGAGACAGCAGGACCAACCCUCCAUCUACUCAAUGGGAAGAUGAUAAGGAUGAAGACCUUUAUGGUGAUCCGCUUCCACUUAAUAAAUAGUAAAUUCAUUAA